ACUGCGAUAGGAAUCAUGUCUGGUCGCGGCAAAGGCGGAAAAGGCUUGGGGAAGGGUGGUGCUAAGCGCCAUCGUAAGGUGCUCCGGGAUAACAUCCAGGGCAUUACAAAACCGGCUAUUCGCCGUUUGGCUCGGCGCGGUGGCGUCAAGCGCAUUUCCGGUCUUAUCUAUGAGGAGACUCGAGGUGUGCUUAAGGUUUUCUUAGAGAACGUUAUUCGAGACGCCGUCACCUAUACGGAGCACGCCAAGCGCAAAACUGUCACAGCCAUGGAUGUAGUAUAUGCCCUAAAACGUCAGGGGCGCACUCUGUAUGGCUUCGGCGGCUGAAUCUAAGAAUACGCGGUCUCCUGAGAACUUCAAAAAACAAAAACAAAAAAACCCAAAGGCCCUUUUCAGGGCCGCUCA